AUGGCACAGGUGAGGGCGCUGCAUAAAAUCAUGGCCCUUUUUUCUGCUAACAGCAUAGGUGCUAUGAACAACUCUGACACUCGCAUAGCAGGCUGCUUCCUCACUGGCAUCCCUGGGCUGGAGCAACUACAUAUCUGGCUGUCCAUCCCCUUCUGCAUCAUGUACAUCACUGCCCUGGAAGGCAAUGGCAUCCUAAUUUGUGUCAUCCUCUCCCAGGCAAUCCUGCAUGAGCCCAUGUACAUAUUCUUAUCUAUGCUGGCCAGUGCUGAUGUCUUGCUCUCUACCACCACCAUGCCUAAGGCCCUGGCCAAUUUGUGGCUAGGUUAUAGCCUCAUUUCCUUUGAUGGCUGCCUCACUCAGAUGUUCUUCAUUCACUUCCUCUUCAUUCACUCUGCUGUCCUGCUGGCCAUGGCCUUUGACCGCUAUGUGGCCAUCUGCUCCCCCCUGCGAUAUGUCACAAUCCUCACAAGCAAGGUCAUUGGGAAGAUCGUCACUGCCGCCCUGAGCCACAGCUUCAUCAUUAUGUUUCCAUCCAUCUUUCUCCUUGAGCACCUGCACUAUUGCCAGAUCAAUAUCAUUGCACACACAUUUUGUGAGCACAUGGGCAUUGCCCAUCUGUCCUGUUCUGAUAUCUCCAUCAAUGUCUGGUAUGGGUUGGCAGCUGCUCUUCUCUCCACAGGCCUAGACAUCAUGCUUAUUACUGUUUCCUACAUCCACAUCCUCCAAGCAGUCUUCCGCCUCCUUUCUCAAGAUGCCCGCUCCAAGGCCCUGAGUACCUGUGGAUCCCAUAUCUGUGUCAUCCUACUCUUCUAUGUCCCUGCGCUUUUUUCUGUCUUUGCCUACAGGUUUGGUGGGAGAAGCGUCCCAUGCUAUGUCCAUAUUCUCCUGGCCAGCCUCUACGUUGUCAUUCCUCCUAUGCUCAAUCCCGUUAUUUAUGGAGUGAGGACUAAGCCAAUACUGGAAGGGGCUAAGCAGAUGUUUUCAAAUCUUGCCAAAGGAUCUAAAUAA